AGCGCGCCCGGCACUCUCGGCGGUCCGGGCCCCUCGCCACUACCGCCGCCGCCGCCGCCGUGAGUCCCGCGGAGCCGCGCGCGCCCCCGGCUGGGCCGAGCCGCUGGCCGACGAGCGGAGCCUCAGGAGCCGGCGGGGACGCCAUGCGAGCCAGAUCCCUCCUGUGAGGAUGAAAUUGAAAACUCCGGUUUCUGGCUUGGCGAUCGGGUGACCGAGCAGCCGCGAGGUGACAGCGCCGGCGGCCCGCGGGCGGGGACCGGCUGGGAUAGAGGCGCGUUGUUCUCUGAGCGAUGUUUACCGAGAAGCCCGCUCCGCGGCACGGGCGGGUGUCAGUUGGGACCCCAACCCUGGGUCCCGCGGCUCCUAGCCCGGGGCCUGCGGUGUAGACGGGGGUUGGGGACAGGCCCAGCUGGCCCUGACCGGGUGUCGGGCGCCCAGAGAUGCCGCGCGGGAGGAGCCGCGGGAGAGCCGCCGGACUCAGCGAGCAGAGGGUCGUGGAGCCUGAUGGAUCGAUGAGAUCUGAAAAAGAACACUGUGCGAGAUUGUAUUCCUGCUUAUUCUUUCCAAGUUAGUAGGCAGAUUGGAACUAUAGAAUUUAUCCGUGAUAAUAAUAAAGUUCGCAUAACUUUUGUUCUGAUUACAGAAACAAUGUAUGCUCAGGACAGAAAGCUAGAGAUAAAGAGAAAUAUAAACAGCAAACAGGAAACCAUCCCCAAUCCCACAUUUUUUACCAGCCUUGUCACAGCCUGGCAGAUUUGAACAUUAAGUUAGAACUGGAGCCAUUCUUGCCUAAACCAGAGAAUCCCUGAAUGCAGCCGCCCCUUCUCACCCUUGUGACCGUCUCUGAGCUCCAAAGUUUGGGUUUUUUCCUUGCUCCCUACCCGGGCAGAAUCUCUGCUGGCCACGAGUCCCCUUCCCAGUGGGCUGGGGGCUUUCCUUGAGAUCCGUGGCCCAGAUGAAAUGAUGGGAGAGGCCUGGAUCCUCACCGCCCUCUGUGGUUUUGGUUCCUUGCCUUGUAAAAAUGAAGGUAAUGAUUCUCAAUCUGCUUCUCAAGCCACCAUAAAAAUUAAUGGGUGGUUUGCAGAGCGUUUUGACAUCCGUGGAUGGACAGCGGCUGUACUUUAAGGCGCUGGGGAACAUUCUACUGUUCCUCAUUGCAGUGGUCAUGCAGUGUAAUAGGCUGCCUCUCACCUGGCCGUCCUGCCCAGGAAACAGACUCCAGGAAUGUCCAGUGGAGCCCUGAGGACAAUAUUCCUGGUUCCUUGCUCAGUGCCCUCGGGACUCGGCCAAAUCCCUCAGAGUGGGAAGCUUGGGAAGAGGCAGCGCUCUCCAAUCCCCCUCCUCCACCUCUGCUUUCUGCUUGUAGGCGGAUUUCUUAAAGUAAGGGGGCAGUGAUAUUUAGGCGGGACCCCAGAUUGCCCACUGCCUGAUGUUUGUGGGUCUGUGGAAUGCCCGGGCCGUGCUUAUCCAAAAGAACAGUUAGUUCUGGGAGGACGCAUAAACUGAACAAACCUGGCUUCCUAGAGAUUUGUAUGGCUCACUUGUUUACUAAAUGAACAAUGACCGGCUGCGGAGAAGCCCAGGACACUUCUGUGAGCUUUAUUAUUAUUUUUUUCCUGUUGUCCCAAGACUACAUUUUAGUGAUCUUAUAAAACAAUAAAUAAGAACCCAUGCCAUUUGUUAAUUCUGGGUACCAAAGGCCCAGGUGGGGAGAGGUACUUCACAGCAUGCCUUUUGUCCCCAAGCACCCAUGCCACCCCCACAACAACAAAGUAAUCAGGGUAGAAGAUCCUCUUUCUGUAACCGUCUGUCGUUUGAUAGUUUCAUUUUUUAAAUUGUCCUUUCCACCAGCACGUGGAUCUGAUCAGGGUCUGUCUAGUUGCAGAUCACAGCUCAAGAGGGGGUUUUGGAAAGACCCAGAAAGUGGGCUGAAAAAAAUGCUGAUAAAGUAUCCUUCACCGGGUGCCUUGUCUGUUCAUGUAUUGUGCUCUUACUUUUCUCUGUGGAGGGAGGACCUUCCUGGCUUUUCUCCCUUGCUCUUGUUUGCUAAUCCGGCAGCCUGGAAUUAUUUCCCUCUGGGCUGCUUGAAUAGACUUUCUUCUUAUUCUAAUGCUGGAUUCUAGUCUGAUCAUAAGAUAUGCGAAUGGUGAAUGUGGUUUACGCCCUUGAAUCCUGGGAGGUGUUCCUGGUUUUAAAUCCUGGGAUCCUGGCCAGUUAAGAGCCCCUGGCUCCCCUGAAAUUGCGUGGGAGGUGUGUGUGCUUUCUUUUCCUGGGGAGCUUCUUACAGAGCCCUUGACCCAAACAAGGUUGAGAGCUCCAGAGUGCGGCCCUGGCAGACCUCGUCCCUGGACCCUGGCUCCAGGCAGACCUCCCAGUUCCAGCCUCGUUUCAGGUACCAGCCUUGUUUUGACCGAGUAGGAGCUGCUGUUUACAACUGGCCAGCCAUGUGGAUUUCCCUUAGCUUUAUUAUUUUCAAAUUGCACACCUAAAUUGGGCUGUGUUGUGAUUUUUCUUCUGCAAAUUGGACUCAGGCCCCUGGGACAUUUCCCAAGGCCCUGGAGGUGGGCAUCAGGUCUUCUCUGUUGCGAGGUAGCCGCCUGACAACCAGGAAUCCGAAAAGGUCACCGAUCACUAAAUAGAGUUCUCAGAGCACUCUCAGUGCGCGGGUCAGCUUUGCUCCUGGCCAGGAGCGAGCCUCAGGCCAAGCAACGUUUACACUCAGCUUCUGGGGAGCUGGGCUAGGUCUCUGGGCUCCCCAGCUAUUUGCACGAAAGAAGCCUCACAUUCUGCCACCACCCUGUGGAGCAGUGACAGAAAAACAAUUCAUCUAGCCCCCAAAUACCCAGGGAACAAUCCAGCUACUUGAUUCAGUAUCCUCCAGGAAGCCGAAACCAGCUCCUCGGUGGGCCCUGAGGGCGUCCACGUGUUACAUAACCCAGCACCUGAUCCCACCGUGACCUCGCUAAAGGGAAAAAGUCUCAAUAAUCAGUCUUCAGAGGGCGAGGGAGUGCAGAAUAUGCUUUAGAAAGAGGCUGUGUGCCGUGUUUUAAGAAGGGUAAAAUCCCAUGUAGAACAUCACAGCCUCCCAUCUUCCAGGUGAACAGUGCCUCCUGAAGUCAUCAGGAAGCAUAUGGAUUUGAGGAAGUAGAAUUGCUGUAUGGAAUUCCUCUAAUUUAAGGUUUGGGGUAUUUUGAGGGAUGGAAAUAGGUACCACUCGUUGAGGGCUUACCAUAUGCUAGGCUGCAUGUGUGCCCUUUUGAAUCCUCACGAAAACUACCAGGGGUUUCAUUUUACAGGGAAGCUACGAGAAUUUAAGAAACUCCUCCAACCUUAGACUUUAAUGAGUGCUUGAGUUGGGAUUUGAACCUGGAUCUGUCCAAGUCCAGAGCUCGUCAUCACAUCUCCCGGGGUGCUGAAAUUAAAGAAACAAACGGCUCUCAGUCACACAUUGGAGCCUGAAGAUACAGGCAUGCAAAUAGCGGAGUGCCAGCCUCCCUCACACAAUUAGAAAAUAGCUUGUACUCUGAAGGUGAUGAAAUCUUUAAAACAUGUGACGCUUUCUCAGCCUAAAUGGAAGGCAGCCAUUUUGCACCUUUGUUCGUGAAACCCUCACCCCGUCACCAGGGCGAAGCAAGGUUUAUUUGGAAGAUUGUGACUUUGAAGUUGGGAUAACCCAGGAUUUGGUACGAUGUCUUUCCUUGUCCCGUGAAAAGAGGGUGUUUGGGCACAUGGGGUCACUAGAAUGAGAUUAAGAUUAUAGGAAGGCGGUUAAGUAAAUGUACAAUAAGGGUUCCACCUUCCUCUUUACAAUCAAAUAAAUGACAUACUAAUGAGAUUAUUCUUAUCUGCGCAAUAAAAGCUUAUCUCAGGGGAGCUCUCUUUGCUGAAGCCUGUUAGCCCAACUCUUCUGUAGAGAUUGAGAAGAAUACUUCCUUUGAAAGGAUUUUAUGGUUCCAAGUUUUUAUUAAAUCUGCAUAACUGAGGACAACCCUGCCUCUUUUUUUUUUUUUUUUGAGUUGAGAUUUCUCUGUUGCCCAGGCUGGAGUGCAGUGGCUCAAUCAUAGCUCACUGCAGCCUUCAACUCCUGGGCUCAAGCAAUCCUUCUUCCUCAGCCUCCUGAGUAGCUGGAACUACAGGUGCACACCAGCACGCCCGGGUAGUUUUUUUUUUUAAAUUCUUGUAGAAAUGGGGUUUCGCUAUGUUGUCCAGGCUGGUCUUGAACUCCUGGUUUCAAGUGAUCCUCCAGCCUUGGUCUCCCAAAGCACUGGGCUUACAGGUGUGAGGUAUGUUGCCCUGCCCUUGCCCCAUUUUUAUGAGCAGGCAGGAAGCUUUUCUAGCCCCUCCAAUGUAGGAGGUCCCUGAGCUCAUAGUGUGCCGGUAAACCUGCUCUCUGAGGAGAAAGCAGAGCUUCGAUUGCAGUAUCUGCCAAUUUCUGUGACGUAAAUAUUCCCACCAUGGCUAAUUUCUUUUUCUUUUUUUUGAGUCUCACUCUGUCACCCAGGCUGGCUGGAGUGCAGUGGUGCAAUCUCGGCUCACUGCAACCUCCACCUCCCAGAUUCAAGCUGUUCUCCUACCUCAGCCUCCUGAGUAGCUGGGACAACAGGCAUGUGCCACCACGCCCAGAAGUUUUUGUAUUUUUAGUAGAGACCGGCUUCCCCAUGUUGGCUAGGCUGGUCUUGAACUCCUGACCUCAGGUGAACGGCCCAGCUUGGCCUCCCAAAGUGCUGGGAUUACAGAUGCAAGCCACCAUGCCCAGCCUGAUUUCAAACUGCCAGUUUGGGCUGGGAACAUUACUAAAUAGUUAACAAUCUGUGUGAGCCAAGAAGAGCUGGGUCCUGCUCACCAUUCAUUGCACUGAGCCCACCCACACGACACCCCUGCUUCCCCUUCCGUCACCCCCAUCACUUUAAUGGAAGAAAUUGUGGCCUCACUUCUGCUUGGUCCAUGUCUGCCUAGGAGCAGUACUGAAAAAGGAUUUGGGUACUACUGAGUAACCGAAUUUGGCCAGCAAGAGUAGAAGGCUUCAAAACUCAGGCUGCAUUUUAAAAUCACCCGGGAGCUUAAAAAAACAACAAUCCAUGUUCCAGGCCCAUCCCCAGUUGAAUCAGAAUGUCUGGGUGUGGGUCCAGACCUCUGUAGAUUUGGAAAGCUUCCCGGGUGACUGUAAUGUAUAUCCACGUUGAACACCAGGGAUGUGGUGAUGAAUUUGUUCAAGAAGAAAGCUGAGGGGGUGCAGUUUGGGGCAGGGCGUGGCAGACCCUGUGUAUUUGAGCCCAAGGAGGUGAGAUCUCCCUUGCAGAGCAGGGAAUGUUUUUCCUUAAGGCCUCGUAGAGGGUGAGGAAGUGCUGGGCUAGGAGAGGCAGGCGGAGCCCAUCUUCCCCCCAACAGGUCUGUCCUCCUCCAGGGGCACGUGUCCUACACUGAUGAGGUCCACAUACUUGUUUGGCUUUGGUUGCUUCUGCUGGUCUAGAAAGGAAAAGAGUCUUCCUUCCAGGAAGUCAGGGGGUCAGGAUGAAGCCAGGCAGACCCCCUGGGUGGGUGUGAUGAGCUGUUCUCAGAUAUUAAAGCAGAGGGGCUUACUGGGACCACCCAGAUGAAGGAAAGAGAAACCCUACCGCCCAAGGACCAUAGCUGAACACUUUGUAAGAGUCCUUGAGCUUGGGUGCGCACAUAAGCUGAUUAUUUUUUCUCCAUCAUAAUUACCAGUAAAAUUAUUUUAAAAUGUGAGAGCUUUCCUUGGAGGCAGUAAGCAUGUGGGAGGGAAAAGUCAUUCAACUUCAGAGCCAGCCAUGGUGAGCGGGGCUGGGACUGGGGAGAGGCACACGAGGCCCCUGGGGUGCAGGAUUCAAGGAGGUGCUCGCCCUGGGGGGGUGUCUGGGGAAGGGUCUGUCCUGCUGGCCAGAGGAGGGCUGUUUGAGAGAGGGCGGUCCUGGGCUCACUUCCUUAGAGUUGGGCAGUGAGUGUGGAAGAGCUCAUACAUGGGAACCUAGAGUGAAGAGCAGGGGCCAGGAUCACACUGCUGGAUCACCCCCAGAAGGGGCAGGAAGGCUAAGGGGGAGCCAGUGGAGGAGCAGCUGGGAUGGGAGAACAAGUGCCCUGCGGGGCCCUGAAGUCAAGGAGGAGAAAGAUGGGGGUAGGGGGAGAGGGGGUUGAGAGCUCAAAGCAGACGGGACAGUUCUGAGUCUAUCAUGUGCGGAGGAUUUAUGAACGGGAGGACUGGAACCCUGUCACUGUGGUAGUGGAGAAACUCCUAUAAUAGAAGAAAUAGCACAGAGUGGAGGCCACGCAGAAGAAUGUUGGUGAUAAAAGAAAUUGGACCGUAUUUGAUGGUGUGGAGACAGGGCAGGAGGGAGCCAGGGUUGGGUCAGAGGGACUGGGAUUCUAGCAGGGGCGGAAAAUUCUCCUUGGGGUACCCGUGCGGUGGGGAGUGGCCGCAGAUGCUGAGAGGGAAGCAUUGGGUGUGAAUAGCUGAUCACCAGGAGCAGCUGGUUAAAAGACCUUCCCCAAAUGCUUUCUCAGAUCAUAACAUCUGCAACUUUUUCCCACUAGCCUUUGUGGAGGGCUGGCUGGGGGGCCCAUUUGUCCUUAAGACUCAAUUCAGCAGACUCACUUGCUCUUCCAGGCCCAGUUCACACUGCCUUCUCAGACACACCCGAGGAACCUGCACCUGGGUCUGCCUGUGUCCUAGCUUUCUUACCUGUCUGUUGUCCCCCUAGGCAGGGCGCUGCUUGGGGGCAGUUGCAUUUUAUUAUCUCUGCAUCCUCCAUACACAGGAGCCCCUCAGACACCAUGCCCAGUGCAUGAAAGAGCUGGCAGAGAGAGAGAGAGAGCCUGGACAAGGUGAAAACUUAGGGUGGUGACUUCAUACAGCCAUGUAGUGACAACUCCAAUAUUCUCUUCUUGACAUCUUGGCAGUAAAACUUACAAUAUAUGAUAGAAGUAAUUCCUCCCUAUGAAUAAUAAACGGCUUACUUAUAAAUACUGUCCAGUGGCCAUCCCCGUAGUUCUGUGCAAUUUAAUUUUUAAUUCAGGUAGGUUUACCUUGCCUUUGUUUACCCAUUUUCCACUGUUGCCCUUUGUAAGAGGAUUUGACUUUUUUUUUUUUUUUUUUGAGACGGAAUCUCACUCUUGCCCACGCUGGAGUGCAAUGGCACGAUCUCGGCUGAUUGCAACCUCCGCCUCCUGGGUUCAAGUGAUUCUCCUGCCUCAGCCCCCCAAGUAGCUGGGAUUACAGGCGCAUGCCACCAUGCCUGGCUAAUUUUUGUGUUUUCAGUAGAGGUGGGGUUUUACCAUGUUGGCCAGGCUGGUCUUGAACUCCUGACCUCAGUUUAUCUGCCCACCUCGGCCUCCCAAAGUGCUGGGAUUACAGGCAUGAGCCACCUUGCCCGGCGAGGAUUUGAUUUUUUAAAAGCUUUAAGAUUAAGAGAUAAAUGGAGUAUUAUUAAAAUGCAUGUACAUUUAAGCAUUUUUAAAUCCUGCUAACAAUCAUAGUUGAUGUACAAGUGCCGUCAAAUAUUUGUAUGUGUCCUGUGCAUAAAUGGGAAAUAAGGGUACGGUAUUCAGAUCUAACUGAAAAUAAUGAUUGGAGCUGAUGUAAUACUUACACAUAAUUCAUGUAGAAUGCUAGGCCCAGGGCCUAUGCCCCAUUGCAAAGUGGUGAAUACAGAUAUGGUUGUGGUUCUUCCUGCUGUGGUCUGGUCUCACGUUUCCUUACCCCUGUCCCAAAUAUCCCCUCUAGCAAGUUGGGUUUUUGUUUUUAUCUUGUGGUUUGAGGAAUCGAUAUUUCAAAUGUUUGUAAGAGGAAUGCUCUGUUCCGGUUCAGUACAGAGCAGCAGCCAUUGGUUCUCUCCUUUACAGUGUGGGACUAGGACAUCAACACAAUUUUGAAUUUUGGUCUCAUUUCAGGCCUGUGUGAGGGGGUGCUGACUCUGGGUGACAUCAGGAGAUCAGGCACUGGCUAGUCAUCACAAACAGAAUCCCAAGAGUUCACUUAGUGCCCAUUUUUGCUUAUAUGUGUAUCUUAUUGGAGCCACCUGUGAUUUUCAGAACUGCUGAAUUGGGGGAAAGCAGACGCAACUGUUUGGGGCCACGUGCGCACACACUUGAAAUGCUCAGUUGCACUGUGUAAUGUAGGAUUUUUCCGUGGUUUUGGAUUCUUCCCAUUUUUGUUGGCCUUUUCCCUGUGUUACGCACUGAGACACUUCUGUACACAGCUGUUUCUUCGAAAUCAAUCAAAUUUGAAACAGCCUGAUUUGCAAAACUGAAAGUUGUUGUAUGGAGGAAGAUCCUUGGUAAGAAUUACAUGGCUCACGUAUCAUGUUCUUCUUACAUUGUUUUUUGUUUCCCAGCCAUUGUCAGGGAACAAUAGCUGGAAUGACGUUUUCACAGACUGCAAUAUGAGAAGUUCCUUUUUCCAGUGGCAGCUCCAUGGCUCUUUGUUGGGACCUGGUUCAUUGCGGGGACAUCACAGUGGGAAAGAGCAGGGGGUGUCUGAGCCCCACACACCUGUCUGUGUCCGAAUAUUUGGCUUCUCUUCCUGUUAUGACCUCGGUCACAUUUUUGGACAUCUUUGAGGCUCAGCCUUCUGAUCUCUAAAAUGAUGACCAUCGUACUUCGCUCCUGGAGUUGGGCAGUUUAAAUGAGAUCACACUCAAUGCCACUGUACUGCUAGCUGUGGAUUUGGCUCCAUCAUUGUCCCUGUGGUUUUUGUUUGUUUGUUGUUUGUUUUUGAGAUGGAGUUUUGCUCUGUCGCCCAGGCUGGAGUGCAGUGGUGCGAUCUUGGCUCACUGAAAUCUCCACCCACUGAGUUGAAGUGAUUCUCCUGCUUCAGCCUCCCAAGUAGCUGGGAUUACAAGUGUGCGCCACCAUGCCCAGCUAAUUUUUGUAUUUUUAGUAGAGACGGGGUUUUACCAUGUUGGCCAGGCUGGUCUCGAACUCCCGACCUCAGGUGAUCCACCUGCCUCAGCCUCCCCGGGUGCUGGGAUUACAGGUGUGAGCCACUGCGCCCGGCCUCCAUGUUGGUUUUGAGCCCCAUGCUUGUCAGCGUGCAGUUCAUCAUGCCUUGCUUCUUUUGUCUUGUGUACAUGUACCAUAGUUUAUUCUUAGAUACUGAGUUAAUAGAAUUUCUGUGAUGUUCCAGCAUCUGAGUUGAACAGAGUGUAAGGGUUUGAUAUUCUUCUGAUGCUCAACUUGACCUUUAAAAAGCUCGUAGGUGUGGACCAGGGGCUCGAUGCAGUCCUAAGUGUCUAAAUAAGGUUUAGGGCUCAUCCAUGCCAACUUUGCCCAGUUCCUGAAGUUCCUGGAGGAGGUGGGGUGGUGGGGGUGGGGGUGGGGGUGAGGAGGGGGAUGUGUUUGAUGAGGCUACAGGUCCCCAGACCUGGGGUGGAGUGUGGCUCUGGCAGGUAGCAUAGAAGGACCAGCAGCAAGUGCCGGAGGCCCCUGUGCCUUUGUUUGCAAGAGGUCUUUACCUGCCCUGACUUCUUGGGUGGGGUGGGGAGGUGAUAACAUCUUUUGUUCACUGUAAGUACUUUGUAGACAUAUGAGUUGUUUUCAGAAUUGUUCCUUGUGAUUUUCUUUCAGCUUUUGGUUUUUUUGGAGACAGUGUCUCCCUCUCUCACCCAGACUGGAGUGCGGUGGCCCAAUGUCAGCUCACCACAACCUCCGCCUCCCAGGUUCAAGUGAUUCUUGUGCCUCAGCCUCCCUAGUAGCUGGGAUUAGAGGUGCAUGCCACCACGCUCGGGUAAUUUUUGUAUUUGUAGUAGAGAUGGGGGUUUCACUGUGUUGGCCAGGCUGGUCUUGAACUCCUGACCUCAAGUGAUCUGCCCGCCUUGGCCUCCCAAAGUGCUGGGAUUACAGGUGUGAGCUACUGUGCCUGGCCUCUUCUUUUCCAAAAAAAAUAAUAAUAAAAAAACCUUUUCUGCUUAUGUAUUUUAAAUUACUGAAUAAAUUACAUGUUUGUACAUGUUUGUUUUAGAAACACUAGAAAAUGUAAAAAGAAAAAAAAUCACAUCAGUGGAAUUCUACCACCCAUGAUGACCACUCUGGACACUUUCAUAUGCGUCUUUCAGAUAUUUUCGCUUGAAGUAUAGAGCUUCCAAACAAAAACAGGCUGAGACAGUGAGUGGUCUUGCCUUUGUACCUGGCACAUAGCAAUUUUUCAAUAAGUAUUUAUUGAAUGAAUACUAUGCUUUUUUUUUUUGAGACUUUUUAGGCUGGAGUGCAGUGAUGUAAUCUCAGUUGACUGCAACCUCCGCCUCCUAGGUUCAAGCGAUUCUCCCGCCUCAGCCUCCCUAGUAGCUGGGAUUACAGGCACUUGCCUGUAAUUUUAAUAUUUUAGUAGAGACACAGUUUCUACUAAUUUUAAUAUUUUAGUAGAGACACAGUUUCACCAGGCUGGCCAGGCUGUUCUCAAACUCCUGAUCCCAAGCGAUCCAACUGCCUCAGCCUCCCAAAGUGCUGGGAUUACAGGCGUGAGCCACCACGCCCGGCAAUGCUAUGCUUUUAAAAAUAGCUUUUUAUCUAAAAUUGUUGACAUAUUUUCAGAUCAAUAAAUACAGAUUUGCAUCCUCAUUUUUCAUGUCAGGUUUGUAUAGGUACAGGUACAGUACCCUGUUUGUUUAAUAAGUGUUUGUGAAUAGACACUUCCCAGUUAUUUUGAAAUUAUAAACAACACUGCAAUGAACAUCUUUGAUAUAUAGAUUUUUCCAUGCAUGUUAAGUUUCUCAUUUGAAUGAAUCUUUUACUUUUAUUGUGCUUAAAAUCUAUGAAGAACUUAUAAUUAUAUUAAUUGUUGGGUGACUGUAUAAUUACUAUACAGAAAAGCACCUCAAAAGGGAGUGACGUUGGGAAGAGUUCCAGAAUCUGUUGUAUAAAACUUGGUGAACUUUAAGAGCGGCCGUACUUGUUCCCAUCCUUUUUGGGGGAAUGCUUUCUGUUUCUCCAGAUCCUGACGUGCUUUGCGUUCUGCGCUUUUGGAGUGGGAGGGUGGGUCAACAGAGUAAUGUUGAUGCCUUAAACGCAUACUUCAGUUUUAGGAUGCACACAUACAUGCCAGCUUCAGAAGCAUUAACAUCUGGGAGUAACUGUAUGUUCUAGAGUCCAGGAGGUGUUUCCGUUGGGAGGUCUUCAGGGCCCACUCCCUCCUAGAAGGGGAUGAGUGAUGGUUUUCAUGCAUUCAGCUUCGGAGCUGUUGUUGUAAGCUUCUCCAGGGUCAUGUCGUCAUGGGUGUCCAGAGUGAUUUUGUGGCUGUGUCACUUGAUCAGCUGUGACAAGAUGGACUGCAGUUGGAUCUGGCAUCUGGUAAAAGCACAGACUUGGUUUUCAGGACCUCUGGGUUCACUAAGGGGAGAGUUUGUCAUGGCUCCUGCUGAUCGCAAGACUGUAAUUUGGAUCUUGACUGCGGUCUGGUGUCGCAAGCCUUCUUUCUGGCAAGAGAGGAAAACUAAUUUAUGGGCGGAAUAUUUUUUGGCCUGUCUCCUGUAGUUUUGCACAGGGGCCUGGCUGCCUCCUCAGGUCUUGGCACCGCAGUAUUUGUGAGUCAUCCACCUAUAGGUAACAUGAGGCAGCACUUUGGGGCUUCGUGAAACCCCAGCUAUGGGGAUAAGGGACUGGCCAGCAUUCCCAGCACGCCCCAGGGGCUGCUUAGAAGCAGGAAACUGUCCAUGAGUUCUGGUUUUUUGUUCUGAGUGUGGAGGACACCUUCAGGAGGCUGGGGAGGGGCCCUGACAUCAAGCCUGAGAGCUGACCCCUUUUCUAACUCUCUGGGACAUGGUCCUGGCUCUUUCCCUCUUCUUGUUCACGCUUUAAUGCCUUUUAAUUCCUUGACUCACUGCUGAGCCCCUCUGCAUUCCGGGUGGGGGAGAUAAAUGGGGAGCCCACCAGAUGCAGCGUCUGCCCACAGGGAGUUCACUGCCCAGCAGGGGAGAAGGGGCAUUCAAGUGCACCAGGGGAAAGGUCAGGGUUCAUGAGGUUGUAGUUGUACUGGGGGUCAGGACAGGAUCCCUAAAGAAGCCCCACUAAGUAGGGGGACCUGAAGAAUGAGCAGGCCAGGAAGUGCAUGGUGAUUUAGGGGGGCAGUGGACUGGUGGGUUCUGGGCAGGGUGGCUUGGUGAGUCCAAGGAACCAAAAGAGGGCCAUAGUGAGACCCCCUUCCCAAGAGCACCUGGGAGGGAUUCCGGGGCAGGUGGCUGGAUCGGACAGGUCCUUCUGCACUUCCCUCGCUUUGAACUUGUAUCUAAGGGCACCAAGAAGACGCGAUUAGACGUGUAAGCGUGACUUGAAAGGGGCCGGGUGACCUGCCUGGGGUUCCCUGGCACAGGGGGUGACCCAUCCAUCAUCGACGCCUGGCAGGGAGGCUACCCUGUGCACCACAUCCUGUUCCAGACCCCCAUCUUCACAGCCCUGGCACUACGUGUAGCAGAGUCGGUCUCCCAGCCCAGUGCUCCCGUGACCCACAUGUGGUACUUCUCCCUCCCGGCCUGCUGUGAGAUUCUUAUAAAAUUGUCUCUGAUUAAUCACCCUGUACAGCUUUUAAAAGUUACUUUUAUUACCCAAAACAACACUUCAGAAACUAAGCUGACGGUUGAAUCAUUGAAGGAGUCACAGCAUUCUUUCAUCCCAGAGAGAAAAAAGGUAAUGAAGAAGAGGAGACUGUCCAGUGAAAACCACAUGAGAGGCACCCAGCAUCAAUGCACCUCUCUCUGGUCAGCUGAGUCCUUGAACUCCUCGGCAGUUCCCCCUCAGGGAAGGUCAGCGGACAGGCUGUGUCCUGGCUUUAAUUGUCAGUUUCUGAAACUCACCAGGCUGGGUAGUCAGACUUCUGACAGCCACUGUCUCUGCACCCCCGUGAGCUGCUGAGUUUACUGGCCAUCCAGAGAGACUUCUGUGUUGAACCCACAUUAACCUGGCUAAUCCCAUCUCUUCUGUGAAAACUUGAAUACAACCUUUUGCAAUAGGAAAACCGGCUGUCCUCAACUGGCUCAGAGGAAAACCAUUAGCUUUUCAAGGUGAAAAGGAAAUAGUGAAAAGCUGGGAGAUGAUGUCAUAAACACUGAUUUUUUUGUCAUUAGUCAAAUUGUCUAGAAAUUGGCUGCUUGCUAAAUUGGGAGUGGGAUCGUUAUUCUGGGAAGAUGGGGGUUUUUUUCAUGCUCAAGAAGAUGGGUAAAAUGGCAGUGAUUUCCACAGCGAACCUGUGUUGGAGGGCUGCGACUAACAGCGUCUCCCUUCUCUCCUGGACAGAAGGCCGUGUCCUGGGACUUCUCUGAUGGCGAGAGGCUGCGGCUGUACCAGGAAGAAACAUAUUGCCGAGUGGAUGCCGCCGCGCAGCGUGUUUGCUUGAGGCAGAAGCUUCAGCAUCUGCUGGGAUAACUGGAGGAAGAAAUAUGAAGCCUUAGCGGCUUUACCCGGGAAGCGAGUUUCGAGAUGGCGGCUCAGCGGAUCCGAGCGGCCAACUCCAAUGGCCUCCCUCGCUGCAAGUCAGAGGGGACCCUGAUUGACCUGAGCGAAGGGUUUUCAGAGACGAGCUUUAAUGACAUCAAAGUGCCUUCUCCCAGUGCCUUGCUCGUAGACAACCCCACACCUUUCGGAAAUGCAAAGGAAGUGAUUGCGAUCAAGGACUAUUGCCCCACCAACUUCACCACACUGAAGUUCUCCAAGGGCGACCAUCUCUACGUCUUGGACACAUCUGGCGGUGAGUGGUGGUACGCACACAACACCACCGAAAUGGGCUACAUCCCCUCCUCCUAUGUGCAGCCCUUGAACUACCGGAACUCAACACUGAGUGACAGCGGUAUGAUUGAUAAUCUUCCAGACAGCCCAGACGAGGUAGCCAAGGAGCUGGAGCUGCUCGGGGGAUGGACAGAUGACAAAAAAGUACCAGGCAGAAUGUACAGUAAUAACCCUUUCUGGAAUGGGGUCCAGACCAAUCCAUUUCUGAAUGGGAACGUGCCCGUCAUGCCCAGCCUGGAUGAGCUGAAUCCCAAAAGUACUGUGGAUUUGCUCCUUUUUGACGCAGGUACAUCCUCCUUCACCGAAUCCAGCUCAGCCACCACGAAUAGCACUGGCAACAUCUUCGAUGAGCUUCCAGUCACAAACGGACUCCACGCAGAGCCGCCGGUCAGGCGGGACAACCCCUUCUUCAGAAGCAAGCGCUCCUACAGUCUCUCGGAACUCUCCGUCCUCCAAGCCAAGUCCGAUGCUCCCACAUCGUCGAGUUUCUUCACCGGCUUGAAAUCACCUGCCCCCGAGCAAUUUCAGAGCCGGGAGGAUUUUCGAACUGCCUGGCUAAACCACAGGAAGCUGGCCCGGUCUUGCCACGACCUGGACUUGCUUGGCCAAAGCCCUGGUUGGGGCCAGACCCAAGCCGUGGAGACAAACAUCGUGUGCAAGCUGGAUAGCUCCGGGGGUGCUGUCCAGCUUCCUGACACCAGCAUCAGCAUCCACGUGCCCGAGGGCCACGUCGCCCCUGGGGAGACCCAGCAGAUCUCCAUGAAAGCCCUGCUGGACCCCCCGCUGGAGCUCAACAGUGACAGGUCCUGCAGCAUCAGCCCUGUGCUGGAGGUCAAGCUGAGCAACCUGGAGGUGAAAACCUCUAUCAUCUUGGAGAUGAAAGUGUCAGCCGAGAUAAAAAAUGACCUUUUUAGCAAAAGCACAGUGGGCCUCCAGUGCCUGAGGAGCGACUCGAAGGAAGGGCCAUAUGUCUCCGUCCCGCUCAACUGCAGCUGUGGGGACACGGUCCAGGCACAGCUGCACAACCUGGAGCCCUGUAUGUACGUGGCUGUCGUGGCCCAUGGCCCAAGCAUCCUCUACCCUUCCACCGUGUGGGACUUCAUCAAUAAAAAAGUCACAGUGGGUCUCUACGGCCCUAAACACAUCCACCCAUCCUUCAAGACGGUAGUGACCAUUUUUGGGCAUGACUGUGCCCCAAAGACGCUCCUGGUCAGCGAGGUCACACGCCAGGCACCCAACCCUGCCCCGGUGGCCCUGCAGCUGUGGGGGAAGCACCAGUUCGUUUUGUCCAGGCCCCAGGAUCUCAAGGUCUGUAUGUUUUCCAAUAUGACGAAUUACGAGGUCAAAGCCAGCGAGCAGGCCAAAGUGGUGCGAGGAUUCCAGCUGAAGCUGGGCAAGGUGAGCCGCCUGAUCUUCCCCAUCACCUCCCAGAACCCCAACGAGCUCUCUGACUUCACGCUGCGGGUUCAGGUGAAGGACGACCAGGAGGCCAUCCUCACCCAGUUUUGUGUCCAGACUCCUCAGCCACCCCCUAAAAGUGCCAUCAAGCCUUCCGGGCAAAGGAGGUUUCUCAAGAAGAACGAAGUCGGGAAAAUCAUCCUGUCCCCGUUUGCCACCACUACAAAGUACCCGACUUUCCAGGACCGCCCGGUGUCCAGCCUCAAGUUUGGUAAGUUGCUCAAGACUGUGGUGCGGCAGAACAAGAACCACUACCUGCUGGAGUACAAGAAGGGCGACGGGAUCGCCCUGCUCAGCGAGGAGCGGGUCAGGCUCCGGGGCCAGCUGUGGACCAAGGAGUGGUACAUCGGCUACUACCAGGGCAGGGUGGGCCUCGUGCACACCAAGAACGUGCUGGUGGUCGGCAGGGCCCGGCCCAGCCUGUGCUCGGGCCCCGAGCUGAGCACCUCGGUGCUGCUGGAGCAGAUCCUGCGGCCCUGCAAAUUCCUCACGUACAUCUAUGCCUCCGUGAGGACCCUGCUCAUGGAGAACAUCAGCAGCUGGCGCUCCUUCGCUGACGCCCUGGGCUACGUGAACCUGCCGCUCACCUUUUUCUGCCGGGCAGAGCUGGAUAGUGAGCCCGAGCGGGUGGCGUCCGUCCUAGAAAAGCUGAAGGAGGACUGUAACAACACUGAGAACAAAGAACGGAAGUCCUUCCAGAAGGAGCUUGUGAUGGCCCUACUGAAGAUGGACUGCCAGGGCCUGGUGGUCAGACUCAUCCAGGACUUUGUGCUCCUGACCACGGCUGUAGAGGUGGCCCAGCGCUGGCGGGAGCUGGCUGAGAAGCUGGCCAAGGUCUCCAAGCAGCAGAUGGACGCCUACGAGUCUCCCCACCGGGACAGGAACGGGGUUGUGGACAGCGAGGCCAUGUGGAAGCCUGCGUAUGACUUCUUACUCACCUGGAGCCAUCAGAUCGGGGACAGCUACCGGGAUGUCAUCCAGGAGCUGCACCUGGGCCUGGACAAGAUGAAAAACCCCAUCACCAAGCGCUGGAAGCACCUCACUGGGACUCUGAUCUUGGUGAACUCCCUGGACGUUCUGAGAGCAGCCGCCUUCAGCCCUGCGGACCAGGACGACUUCGUGAUUUGAAUGGGUCCCCUCCCCUCCUGCUGCUCUGGAGUGCAAGCCCUCUUCUGCCCUGCGUGCCCUGCUGUCACCGCGGAGCUGAAGAGGGAGGAAGGGGCGGCUGCUCAGACAGAUUUAGGGCCCGCCAGCUAGGCUACACCCAUCAUGCGCCGCCCUCCUCCAUCGAGGGAGAGGCCUGAAGGGACUGCCUACUGCAGCUCGUUGCCAAUCACAUAGCUUUCUAUUUGUUAAGUAUAAAUUUAAAUUUAAAAUCACUUUUUUAACGAAUGGGGGGAAGGGAUCUAUGAGAAAGGUGGUAUCUAAUUUUUUUAUGGACCAUAAAGGUUUAAAAGAAAAUAGGGGCACAGGCUGUUGAGGUUUUUAUGUUGUUAUAGACCUUUUUAAAUUAUGUUAGAGAUGUAUAUAGGUAUUUAAAGGUCACUGGGAGCGUUUCUGAUUCCCGGCCACACUUUGCAUUUCAACACUCAGCCCGGAAAGAUGCUCGUUCGGUUGUUGGACCUCUUUCACUCCCUGCGUGUAAGAAGGUGAAUCACGUGGGAAAAAGUGGCUUUUCAGUAAACGGGUACAGCUCAUUCUUUCUGAGAAGGCCCCAGGUCCUGCUCCCUCCUCGGAUUUGAUUGUCUUCCGUGCUUUGCCUCACUCGUAGUAAAUGACCAUCCAUAGAAUAUGUGAAUCUUUGGUGAGCUUCAGUGGGCAGAGUGAAGUCCCGCAUUAGCAUUUAGGUGCCCUGAGCUGUUUCUGCCAAUAGAUUAGAAAGCAGCCAUGAGUUGACAGUCUUUAGGGCCCCUGCCAGUGUGCAAUUAGUCAUUGACAAGAACAAUGCCAUUUGAGAGUGAGGUGGUCCCUGCUGCUACGAGGCCAUUGUACUGUUUUUUCCUUGAGGUCAAAGCAGUGCUUCCCAUAGAGUUUGCUGCCUCUUCUGUGGACAGGAAGAAAACUUCAUGACCGAAUCAGAGCCUUGGUGGCCACUGACUCUCGUGCUUAUUGCAGAUGCUGUGGUUGGCCUCACAAGCAACGCCUUAUGCUGAUGUGCAGAGGUGCCAGCUGCCAUUUGCCAAACUCUGCAUUUCAUUUCAUCUAAGGCUUAACCCCUCUUCCUUCCUGGUGUACCUGUGUCUCCUCGGAAGGAAGUCAUAGUUUAGAUGAAACCAUUUUUUGUACAAUGUAAAGAUCAUCUGAGCAAGAUGAGCAUUUUGUAAAAAUGAAAAUGUGACUCACAUAAAAUCAGGAACUUGACACAGUGUUGCAUUAAUAACUUUAGGGUGCAGACAUGCUGUGUGAAUCUCACAAUGCGUCGUAGAUGUCGCGUGUUGGAAGGGAGCAGGAGGAAGGACUGAUACUGGCAAAUCAGUAGAGUGAGGUGAUCCUUAGCAACGUGCCAGGACACUUCCUGUGUGCCUGCAGUUGUCAGGGACCAUUUGGGAUCCCGAAUCUCAUUCUCUAAAACUGCUUUCUUGAAACAUGUUACUUCCUUAGUAUAAUCAAUGUAUACUCCCUUACUGGCCUGAAACGUUGUAUAGCUACUUAUUCAGAUACUGAAGACCAACGGACUGAAAAAAAGAACAAACAUUAGCUAUUUUAUGCUGCAAGAACCAGGACACACAAUUCGCCAAUCAUCCCACCAUAUAACCUUCGAUUGUGCUUCUCAACUCCACCCCAUAAUUUCUCCCAGAGACCAUCUAUCACCUUUUCCCCAAAGAAGAAACAAAACCAGUUGCACCUUAAACCAUGGAUAUUUUUUCCUCAGGGGCUUUAAAUAGUUUCCUAUGCAACGUGUCUUGUAGCACAAAUAAAAUUCUACAAAAGUUGCAGUAAAUUUUAUUUGGAUAUUUUAACCUGUUAAGUGUGUGUGUGUUUUCUGUACCCAACCAGACUUUAAAUAAAACAAACAUGAAACCUAA